UUUUUUUUUUUUUUUUUUGGUAGAUAAGGGAUUUUGCCAUGUUGCCCAGGCUGGUCUCGAACUCCUGAGCUCAAGUUAUCCACCUGCCUUGGCCUCCCAAAGUGUUGGGAUUACAGGCAUGAGCCACUGUGCCUGGCCAUGCAUGUGUCUUUAUGGCUGAAUGAUUUAUAUUCCUCUGGGUAUAUACCCAGGAAUGAGAUUGCUGGGUUGAAUGGUAGUUCUGUUUUUAGCUCUUUGAGGAAUUGCCAUACUGCUUUCCACAAUGGUUGAACUAAUUUGCACUCCCACCAAAAGUGUAUAAGUGUUCCCUUCUCAACUUGGCCAGCAUCUGUUAUUUUUUAACUUUUUAAUCAUAGCCAUUCUGACUGGUGUGAGAUGGUAUUUCAUUGUGGUUUUAAUUUGCAUUUCUCUAAUGAUAGUGAUAUUGAGCUUUUUUUCAUAUGCUUGUUAGCCACAUGUAUUUUUUUUUUUUUUUUAGAAAAGUGUUCAUGUCCUUUGCCUACUUUUUAAUGGGGUUGUUGUUUUUCUCUUGUAAAUUUAAGUUCCUUAUAGAUGCUGGAUAUUAGACCUUUAUCAGAUGCAUAGUUUGUAAAUAUUUUCUCCCAUUCUUUAGGUUGUCUUUUUACUCUGUUGAGUUUCUUUUGCUGUGCAGAAGCUCUUCAGUUUAAUUAGAUCUCAUUUGUCAAUUUUUGCUUUUGUUGUGAUUGCUCUUAGUGUCUUUGUCAUGAAAUAUUUGCCCAUUCCUGUGUCCGGGAUGGUAUUGCCUAGGUUGUCUUCUGUGGUUUUUAUAGUUUGGGGUUUUACAUUUAAGUCUUUAAUCCAUCUUGAAUUAAUUUUUGUAUAUGGUGUAAGGAGGGGGUCCAGUUUCAUUCUUCUGCAUAUGGCUAGCCAGCUAUCUCAUCAUUUAUUGAAUAGGGAAUCCUUUCCCCAUUGUUUGUUUUUGUCAGCUUUGUCAAAGAUCAGAUGGUUGUAGGUGUGCGGCUUAUUUCUGGGCUCUCUAUUAUGUUCCAUUGGUCUAUGUGUCUGAUUUUGUACUAGUACCAUGCUGUUUUGGUUACUGUAGCCCUGUAGUAUAGUUUGAAGUAGGGUAACAUGUUGCUGUCAGCUUUGUUCUUUUUGCUUAGGCUUGUCUUGGCUAUUUGGGCUUAUUUUUGGUUCCAUAUCAAUUUUAAAAUAGUUUUUUCUAGUUCUGUGAACAAUGUCUUUGGUAGUUUGAUAGGAAUAGCAUUGAAUAUGCAAAUUGCUUUGGGCAGUAUGGCCAUUUCAAUGAUACUGAUUCUUCAUAUUCAUGAGCAUGGGAUGUUUUUCCAUUUGUGUCACUCUGAUUUCUUUGAGCAGUGUUUUCUAAUUCUUUUUUUUUUUGAGAUGGAGUUUCGCUCUUUGUUGCCCAGGAUGGAGUGCAGUGGUGCGAUCUCAGCUCACUGCAACCUCUGCCUCCCAAGUUCAAGUGAUUCUCCUGUCUCAGCCUCCUGAGUAGCUGGGAUUACAGGCGUCUGCCACCACACCCAGCUAAUCUUUGUAUUUUUAGUAGAGAUGGGGUUUCACCAUGUUGGCCAGGCUGGUCUUGAACUCCUGACCUCAGGUGAUCUGCCCGCCUCAGCCUCCCAAAGUGCUGGGAUUACAGGCGUGAGCCACUGAGCCCAGCCUUCUAAUUCUUAUUGUACAGAUCUUUCACCUCCCUGGUUAGCUGUAUUUCUAGGUGAUUUAUUCAUAUUGUGGCAAUCGUGAAUGAGAUUGCAUUUUUGAUUUGGAUCUUGGCUUGGCUGUUGUCAGUGUAUAGGAAUGCUAGUGAUUUUUGUAUAUUGAUUUUCGUAUCCUGAGAGUUGGCUGAAGUUGUUUAUCAACUGAAGGAGCUUUUGGGCCAAGACUAUGGGGUUUUCUAGAUGUAGGAUCAUGUUGUCUGCAAACAGGGGUAGUUUGACUUCCUCUCUUCCUAUUUGGAUGCCUUUUAUUUCUUCCUCUUGCCUGGUUGCUCUGGCCAGGACUUCCAAUAGUAUGUUGAAUAGGAGUAGUGGAAGAGGGCCUCCUUGCCAGUUUUCAAGGGGGGAAUGCUUUCAGCUUUUGCCCAUUCAGUAUGAUGUUGGCUGUGGGUUUGUCAUAGAUGGCUCUUAUUAUUUUGAGGUAUGUUCCUUCAAUACCUAAUUUAUUGAGAGUUUUUAACGUGAAGGGAUGUUGAAUUUUUAAUGAAAGCUUUUCUGCAUGAGAUAAUCAUGUCAUUUUUGUCUUUAGUUAUGCUUAUGUGAUGAAUCAUAUUUAUUGAUUUGCGUAUGUUGAACCAACCGUAAAUCCUGGCGAUGAAGCCUACUUGAUUAUGGUGGAUUAGCUUUUUGAUGUGUUGCUGGACUUGGUUUGCAAGUAUAUUUUUGAGGAAUUUUGCAUCGUUGAUCAAGGAUAUUGGCUUGAAGUUUUCUUUUUUUGUUGGGUCUCUGCCAGGUUUUGGUAUCAGGAUGAUGCUGGCCUCAUAGAAUGAGUUGAGGAGGCGUCCCUCCUCCUUAAUUUUUUUGGAAACCAGGGGUACAGACAAAGUACCCUGUACACCCAACAGUAAUCCCACAGGAGAAGGCAGAGGCCCCAGGCCAUUUAAUCAGCAGCAAGGUGAUUAUGUGAUAUGUCUUUUCACAGUUGAGUUAGAUGUACUCCACCAGUUAUGAUGGGAAUCAAUUUAAAUAUACUUUCUUGAUCCCAGAAAUUCAAGUAUGUGGACAGGAUGUUACACAUGGCAGGAUGAUUGUUACAGCGCAACUAACAUAUUUCAAAUGGACAAAAAAUUAGUAUAAUUUACAGUAUCUUAAGAUAAAUUUCCUUUGAAUGGGAGCUUCCUUUCUAGUCCUUUGAGGUCUACAAGGCAUAUCUAGAAAAUUUACUACUGUGGAAGAUGAAGACUGUUUAAAUUGAAUGGGGGGCAGGAAGGGGAAGGGCCUAUGGUUUUUCUUUUUGAUUAACUGCUGUAACCCUGUCCUUCAGGCAGCUGAAGGAGUGUCACAUUUUCUUUAGACAUCAUUAGGCACCAAAGCUCUUGUAGGACAACUUUGAUGCUACAUGAAUUCUGCCAUUUUGCUAGCACUGAUAUGGCUUUUUGGUCCACCACUCCAUUACAACUAUUAACCCUAUUUAUAUUAAUUUUUGUUACAAAUCUUACAAAGGCAGGGUGCUUCUGGGCAUUUAGGAUACAUUCUAUUUUAAGGCUGUAUACUUGAUUUUCGUAAAUCAUUCUUGGAGGCCCAAUUAUCAUCCCUGUCCAUCUUGUCCCAGGUCUUCAUCAUCUUCUAAACACCAGCUAACUAUGCCACCUCCUACCUUUUUCUGGCCUUCUUCGAGUUCUUCCAUCAGUUGGAAACUUCGAGAGACUUUUACUCCUGAUCCUGUGGUGACUGCCAUCUUGCAUCACUGUUGCCCCAUGUUUUGUAUAAUGAAAAAACUGAGCAAUAGAAAGCAGGUAGUGAUAUAAGAAGUCAACACCGAGAAAUAAGAAAAACAGAAAGCAAAGGGAAACUAAGCAGGACAGUAUGUACUUCAGAAUCAAUUAUUGGUUGCCACCUUUCAGAGGAUGGAGAAGAUAGUUUAUUUACAAAUGUUGGAGUAAUAAAGAAGGCAGAACAAAAUGAGCUGGGCUUUGGAAGAAUGGAAAGAAGGGCUGCCUACAAGAGCUCUUCAGAAAAUUCAAGAGCUUGAAGGACAGCUUGACAAACUGAAGAAGGAAAAGCAGCAAAGGCAGUUUCAGCUUGACAGUCUCGAGGCUGCGCUGCAGAAGCAAAAACAGAAGGUUGAAAAUGAAAAAACCGAGGGUACAAACCUGAAAAGGGAGAAUCAAAGAUUGAUGGAAAUAUGUGAAAGUCUGGAGAAAACUAAGCAGAAGAUUUCUCAUGAACUUCAAGUCAAGGAGUCACAAGUGAAUUUCCAGGAAGGACAACUGAAUUCAGGCAAAAAACAAAUAGAAAAACUGGAACAGGAACUUAAAAGGUGUAAAUCUGAGCUUGAAAGAAGCCAACAAGCUGCGCAGUCUGCAGAUGUCUCUCUGAAUCCAUGCAAUACACCACAAAAAAUUUUUACAACUCCACUAACACCAAGUCAAUAUUAUAGUGGUUCCAAGUAUGAAGAUCUAAAAGAAAAAUAUAAUAAAGAGGUUGAAGAACGAAAAAGAUUAGAGGCAGAGGUUAAAGCCUUGCAGGCUAAAAAAGCAAGCCAGACUCUUCCACAAGCCACCAUGAAUCACCGCGACAUUGCCCGGCAUCAGGCUUCAUCAUCUGUGUUCUCAUGGCAGCAAGAGAAGACCCCAAGUCAUCUUUCAUCUAAUUCUCAAAGAACUCCAAUUAGGAGAGAUUUCUCUGCAUCUUACUUUUCUGGGGAACAAGAGGUGACUCCAAGUCGAUCAACUUUGCAAAUAGGGAAAAGAGAUGCUAAUAGCAGUUUCUUUGACAAUUCUAGCAGUCCUCAUCUUUUGGAUCAAUUAAAAGCGCAGAAUCAAGAGCUAAGAAACAAGAUUAAUGAGUUGGAACUACGCCUGCAAGGACAUGAAAAAGAAAUGAAAGGCCAAGUGAAUAAGUUUCAAGAACUCCAACUCCAACUGGAGAAAGCAAAAGUGGAAUUAAUUGAAAAAGAGAAAGUUUUGAACAAAUGUAGGGAUGAACUAGUGAGAACAACAGCACAAUACGACCAGGCGUCAACCAAGUAUACUGCAUUGGAACAAAAACUGAAAAAAUUGACGGAAGAUUUGAGUUGUCAGCGACAAAAUGCAGAAAGUGCCAGAUGUUCUCUGGAACAGAAAAUUAAGGAAAAAGAAAAGGAGUUUCAAGAGGAGCUCUCCCGUCAACAGCGUUCUUUCCAAACACUGGACCAGGAGUGCAUCCAGAUGAAGGCCAGACUCACCCAGGAGUUACAGCAAGCCAAGAAUAUGCACAACGUCCUGCAGGCUGAACUGGAUAAACUCACAUCAGUAAAGCAACAGCUAGAAAACAAUUUGGAAGAGUUUAAGCAAAAGUUGUGCAGAGCUGAACAGGCGUUCCAGGCGAGUCAGAUCAAGGAGAAUGAGCUGAGGAGAAGCAUGGAGGAAAUGAAGAAGGAAAACAACCUCCUUAAGAGUCACUCUGAGCAAAAGGCCAGAGAAGUCUGCCACCUGGAGGCAGAACUCAAGAACAUCAAACAGUGUUUAAAUCAGAGCCAGAAUUUUGCAGAAGAAAUGAAAGCGAAGAAUACCUCUCAGGAAACCAUGUUAAGAGAUCUUCAAGAAAAAAUAAAUCAGCAAGAAAACUCCUUGACUUUAGAAAAACUGAAGCUUGCUGUGGCUGAUCUGGAAAAGCAGCGAGAUUGUUCUCAAGACCUUUUGAAGAAAAGAGAACAUCACAUUGAACAACUUAAUGAUAAGUUAAGCAAGACAGAGAAAGAGUCCAAAGCCUUGCUGAGUGCUUUAGAGUUAAAAAAGAAAGAAUAUGAAGAAUUGAAAGAAGAGAAAACUCUGUUUUCUUGUUGGAAAAGUGAAAACGAAAAACUUUUAACUCAGAUGGAAUCAGAAAAGGAAAACUUGCAGAGUAAAAUUAAUCACUUGGAAACUUGUCUGAAGACACAGCAAAUAAAAAGUCAUGAAUACAACGAGAGAGUAAGAACGCUGGAGAUGGACAGAGAAAACCUAAGUGUCGAGAUCAGAAACCUUCACAACGUGUUAGACAGUAAGUCAGUGGAGGUAGAGACCCAGAAACUAGCUUAUAUGGAGCUACAGCAGAAAGCUGAGUUCUCAGAUCAGAAACAUCAGAAGGAAAUAGAAAAUAUGUGUUUGAAGACUUCUCAGCUUACUGGGCAAGUUGAAGAUCUAGAACACAAGCUUCAGUUACUGUCAAAUGAAAUAAUGGACAAAGACCGGUGUUACCAAGACUUGCAUGCCGAAUAUGAGAGCCUCAGGGAUCUGCUAAAAUCCAAAGAUGCUUCUCUGGUGACAAAUGAAGAUCAUCAGAGAAGUCUUUUGGCUUUUGAUCAGCAGCCUGCCAUGCAUCAUUCCUUUGCAAAUAUAAUUGGAGAACAAGGAAGCAUGCCUUCAGAGAGGAGUGAAUGUCGUUUAGAAGCAGACCAAAGUCCGAAAAAUUCUGCCAUCCUACAAAAUAGAGUUGAUUCACUUGAAUUUUCAUUAGAGUCUCAAAAACAGAUGAACUCAGACCUGCAAAAGCAGUGUGAAGAGUUGGUGCAAAUCAAAGGAGAAAUAGAAGAAAAUCUCAUGAAAGCAGAACAGAUGCAUCAAAGUUUUGUGGCUGAAACAAGUCAGCGCAUUAGUAAGUUACAGGAAGACACUUCUGCUCACCAGAAUGUUGUUGCUGAAACCUUAAGUGCCCUUGAGAACAAGGAAAAAGAGCUGCAACUUUUAAAUGAUAAGGUAGAAACUGAGCAGGCAGAGAUUCAAGAAUUAAAAAAGAGCAACCAUCUACUUGAAGACUCUCUAAAGGAGCUACAACUUUUAUCCGAAACCCUAAGCUUGGAGAAGAAAGAAAUGAGUUCCAUCAUUUCUCUAAAUAAAAGGGAAAUUGAAGAGCUGACCCAAGAGAAUGGGACUCUUAAGGAAAUUAAUGCAUCCUUAAAUCAAGAGAAGAUGAACUUAAUCCAGAAAAGUGAGAGUUUUGCAAACUAUAUAGAUGAAAGGGAGAAAAGCAUUUCAGAGUUAUCUGAUCAGUACAAGCAAGAAAAACUUAUUUUACUACAAAGAUGUGAAGAAACCGGAAAUGCAUAUGAGGAUCUUAGUCAAAAAUACAAAGCAGCACAGGAAAAGAAUUCUAAAUUAGAAUGCUUGCUAAAUGAAUGCACUAGUCUUUGUGAAAAUAGGAAAAAUGAGUUGGAACAGCUAAAGGAAGCAUUUGCAAAGGAACACCAAGAAUUCUUAACAAAAUUAGCAUUUGCUGAAGAAAGAAAUCAGAAUCUGAUGCUAGAGUUGGAGACAGUGCAGCAAGCUCUGAGAUCUGAGAUGACAGAUAACCAAAACAAUUCUAAGAGCGAGGCUGGUGGUUUAAAGCAAGAAAUCAUGACUUUAAAGGAAGAACAAAACAAAAUGCAAAAGGAAGUUAAUGACUUAUUACAAGAGAAUGAACAGCUGAUGAAGGUAAUGAAGACUAAACAUGAAUGUCAAAAUCUAGAAUCAGAACCAAUUAGGAACUCUGUGAAAGAAAGAGAGAGUGAGAGAAAUCAAUGUAAUUUUAAACCUCAGAUGGAUCUUGAAGUUAAAGAAAUUUCUCUAGAUAGUUAUAAUGCGCAGUUGGUGCAAUUAGAAGCUAUGCUAAGAAAUAAGGAAUUAAAACUUCAGGAAAGUGAGAAGGAGAAGGAGUGCCUGCAGCAUGAAUUACAGACAAUUAGAGGAGAUCUUGAAACCAGCAAUUUGCAAGACAUGCAGUCACAAGAAAUUAGUGGCCUUAAAGACUGUGAAAUAGAUGCGGAAGAAAAGUAUAUUUCAGGGCCUCAUGAGUUGUCAACAAGUCAAAACGACAAUGCACACCUUCAGUGCUCUCUGCAAACAACAAUGAACAAGCUGAAUGAGCUAGAGAAAAUAUGUGAAAUACUGCAGGCUGAAAAGUAUGAACUCGUAACUGAGCUGAAUGAUUCAAGGUCAGAAUGUAUCACAGCAACUAGGAAAAUGGCAGAAGAGGUAGGGAAACUACUAAAUGAAGUUAAAAUAUUAAAUGAUGACAGUGGUCUUCUCCAUGGUGAGUUAGUGGAAGACAUACCAGGAGGUGAAUUUGGUGAACAACCAAAUGAACAGCACCCUGUGUCUUUGGCUCCAUUGGACGAGAGUAAUUCCUACGAGCACUUGACAUUGUCAGACAAAGAAGUUCAAAUGCACUUUGCCGAAUUGCAAGAGAAAUUCUUAUCUUUACAAAGUGAACACAAAAUUUUACAUGAUCAGCACUGUCAGAUGAGCUCUAAAAUGUCAGAGCUGCAGACCUAUGUUGACUCAUUAAAGGCCGAAAAUUUGGUCUUGUCAACGAAUCUGAGAAACUUUCAAGGUGACUUGGUGAAGGAGAUGCAGCUGGGCUUGGAGGAGGGGCUCGUUCCAUCCCUGUCAUCCUCUUGUGUGCCUGACAGCUCUAGUCUUAGCAGUUUGGGAGACUCCUCCUUUUACAGAGCUCUUUUAGAACAGACAGGAGAUAUGUCUCUUUUGAGUAAUUUAGAAGGGGCUGUUUCAGCAAACCAGUGCAGUGUAGAUGAAGUAUUUUGCAGCAGUCUGCAGGAGGAGAAUCUGACCAGGAAAGAAACCCCUUCGGCCCCAGCGAAGGGUGUUGAAGAGCUUGAGUCCCUCUGUGAGGUGUACCGGCAGUCCCUCGAGAAGCUAGAAGAGAAAAUGGAAAGUCAAGGGAUUAUGAAAAAUAAGGAAAUUCAAGAGCUCGAGCAGUUAUUAAGUUCUGAAAGGCAAGAGCUUGACUGCCUUAGGAAGCAGUAUUUGUCAGAAAAUGAACAGUGGCAACAGAAGCUGACAAGCGUGACUCUGGAGAUGGAGUCCAAGUUGGCGGCAGAAAAGAAACAGACGGAACAACUGUCACUUGAGCUGGAAGUAGCACGACUCCAGCUACAAGGUCUGGACUUAAGUUCUCGGUCUUUGCUUGGCAUCGACACAGAAGAUGCUAUUCAAGGCCGAAAUGAGAGCUGUGACAUAUCAAAAGAACAUACUUCAGAAACUACAGAAAGAACACCAAAGCAUGAUGUUCAUCAGAUUUGUGAUAAAGAUGCUCAGCAGGACCUCAAUCUAGACAUUGAGAAAAUAACUGAGACUGGUGCAGUGAAACCCACAGGAGAGUGCUCUGGGGAACAGUCCCCAGAUACCAAUUAUGAGCCUCCAGGGGAAGAUAAAACCCAGGGCUCUUCAGAAUGCAUUUCUGAAUUGUCAUUUUCUGGUCCUAAUGCUUUGGUACCUAUGGAUUUCCUGGGGAAUCAGGAAGAUAUCCAUAAUCUUCAACUGCGGGUAAAAGAGACAUCAAAUGAGAAUUUGAGAUUACUUCAUGUGAUAGAGGACCGUGACAGAAAAGUUGAAAGUUUGCUAAAUGAAAUGAAAGAAUUAGACUCAAAACUCCAUUUACAGGAGGUACAACUAAUGACCAAAAUUGAAGCAUGCAUAGAAUUGGAAAAAAUAGUUGGGGAACUUAAGAAAGAAAACUCAGAUUUAAGUGAAAAAUUGGAAUAUUUUUCUUGUGAUCACCAGGAGUUACUCCAGAGAGUAGAAACUUCUGAAGGCCUCAAUUCUGAUUUAGAAAUGCAUGCAGAUAAAUCAUCACGUGAAGAUAUUGGAGAUAAUGUGGCCAAGGUGAAUGACAGCUGGAAGGAGAGAUUUCUUGAUGUGGAAAAUGAGCUGAGUAGGAUCAGAUCGGAGAAAGCUAGCAUUGAGCAUGAAGCCCUCUACCUGGAGGCUGACUUAGAGGUAGUUCAAACAGAGAAGCUAUGUUUAGAAAAAGACAAUGAAAAUAAGCAGAAGGUUAUUGUCUGCCUUGAAGAAGAACUCUCAGUGGUCACAAGUGAGAGAAACCAGCUUCGUGGAGAAUUAGAUACUAUGUCAAAAAAAACCACGGCACUGGAUCAGUUGUCUGAAAAAAUGAAGGAGAAAACACAAGAGCUUGAGUCUCAUCAAAGUGAGUGUCUCCAUUGCAUUCAGGUGGCAGAGGCAGAGGUGAAGGAAAAGACGGAACUCCUUCAGACUUUGUCCUCUGAUGUGAGUGAGCUGUUAAAAGACAAAACUCAUCUCCAGGAAAAGCUGCAGAGUUUGGAAAAGGACUCACAGGCACUGUCUUUGACAAAAUGUGAGCUGGAAAACCAAAUUGCACAACUGAAUAAAGAGAAAGAAUUGCUUGUCAAGGAAUCUGAAAGCCUGCAGGCCAGACUGAGUGAAUCAGAUUAUGAAAAGCUGAAUGUCUCCAAGGCCUUGGAGGCCGCACUGGUGGAGAAAGGUGAGUUCGCAUUGAGGCUGAGCUCAACACAGGAGGAAGUGCAUCAGCUGAGAAGAGGCAUCGAGAAACUGAGAGUUCGCAUUGAGGCCGAUGAAAAGAAGCAGCUGCACAUCGCAGAGAAACUGAAAGAACGCGAGCGGGAGAAUGAUUCACUUAAGGAUAAAGUUGAGAACCUUGAAAGGGAAUUGCAGAUGUCAGAAGAAAACCAGGAGCUAGUGAUUCUUGAUGCCGAGAAUUCCAAAGCAGAAGUAGAGACUCUAAAAACACAAAUAGAAGAGAUGGCCAGAAGCCUGAAAGUUUUUGAAUUAGACCUUGUCACGUUAAGGUCUGAAAAAGAAAAUCUGACAAAACAAAUACAAGAAAAACAAGGUCAGUUGUCAGAACUAGACAAGUUACUCUCUUCAUUUAAAAGUCUGUUAGAAGAAAAGGAGCAAGCAGAGAUACAGAUCAAAGAAGAAUCUAAAACUGCAGUGGAGAUGCUUCAGAAUCAGUUAAAGGAGCUAAAUGAGGCAGUAGCAGCCUUGUGUGGUGACCAAGAAAUUAUGAAGGCCACAGAACAGAGUCUAGACCCACCAAUAGAGGAAGAGCAUCAGCUGAGAAAUAGCAUUGAAAAGCUGAGAGCCCGCCUAGAAGCUGAUGAAAAGAAGCAGCUCUGUGUCUUACAACAACUGAAGGAAAGUGAGCAUCAUGCAGAUUUACUUAAGGGUAGAGUGGAGAACCUUGAAAGAGAGCUAGAGAUAGCCAGGACAAACCAAGAGCAUGCAGCUCUUGAGGCAGAGAAUUCCAAAGGAGAGGUAGAGACCCUAAAAGCAAAAAUAGAAGGGAUGACCCAAAGUCUGAGAGGUCUGGAAUUAGAUGUUGUUACUAUAAGGUCAGAAAAAGAAAAUCUGACAAAUGAAUUACAAAAAGAGCAAGAGCGAAUAUCUGAAUUAGAAAUAAUAAAUUCAUCAUUUGAAAAUAUUUUGCAAGAAAAAGAGCAAGAGAAAGUACAGAUGAAAGAAAAAUCAAGCACUGCCAUGGAGAUGCUUCAAACACAAUUAAAAGAGCUCAAUGAGAGAGUGGCAGCCCUGCAUAAUGACCAAGAAGCCUGUAAGGCCAAAGAGCAGAAUCUUAGUAGUCAAGUAGAGUGUCUUGAACUUGAGAAGGCUCAGUUGCUACAAGGCCUUGAUGAGGCCAAAAAUAAUUAUAUUGUUUUGCAAUCUUCAGUGAAUGGCCUCAUUCAAGAAGUAGAAGAUGGCAAGCAGAAACUGGAGAAGAAGGAUGAAGAAAUCAGUAGACUGAAAAAUCAAAUUCAAGACCAAGAGCAGCUUGUCUCUAAACUGUCCCAGGUGGAAGGAGAGCACCAACUUUGGAAGGAGCAAAACUUAGAACUGAGAAAUCUGACAGUGGAAUUGGAGCAGAAGAUCCAAGUGCUACAAUCCAAAAAUGCCUCUUUGCAGGACACAUUAGAAGUGCUGCAGAGUUCUUACAAGAAUCUAGAGAAUGAGCUUGAAUUGACAAAAAUGGACAAAAUGUCCUUUGUUGAAAAAGUAAACAAAAUGACUGCAAAGGAAACUGAGCUGCAGAGGGAAAUGCAUGAGAUGGCACAGAAAACAGCAGAGCUGCAAGAAGAACUCAGUGGAGAGAAAAAUAGGCUAGCUGGAGAGUUGCAGUUACUGUUGGAAGAAAUAAAGAGCAGCAAAGAUCAAUUGAAGGAGCUCACACUAGAAAAUAGUGAAUUGAAGAAGAGCCUAGAUUGCAUGCACAAAGACCAGGUGGAAAAGGAAGGGAAAGUGAGAGAGGAAAUAGCUGAAUAUCAGCUACGGCUUCAUGAAGCUGAAAAGAAACACCAGGCUUUGCUUUUGGACACAAACAAACAGUAUGAAGUAGAAAUCCAGACAUACCGAGAGAAAUUGACUUCUAAAGAAGAAUGUCUCAGUUCACAGAAGCUGGAGAUAGACCUUUUAAAGUCUAGUAAAGAAGAGCUCAAUAAUUCAUUGAAAGCUACUACUCAGAUUUUGGAAGAAUUGAAGAAAACCAAGAUGGACAAUCUAAAAUAUGUAAAUCAGUUGAAGAAGGAAAAUGAACGUGCCCAGGGGAAAAUGAAGUUGUUGAUCAAAUCCUGUAAACAGCUGGAAGAGGAAAAGGAGAUACUGCAGAAAGAACUCUCUCAACUUCAAGCUGCACAGGAGAAGCAGAAAACAGGUACUGUUAUGGAUACCAAGGUCGAUGAAUUAACAACUGAGAUCAAAGAACUGAAAGAAACUCUUGAAGAAAAAACCAAGGAGGCAGAUGAAUACUUGGAUAAGUACUGUUCCUUGCUUAUAAGCCAUGAAAAGUUAGAGAAAGCUAAAGAGAUGUUAGAGACACAAGUGGCCCAUCUGUGUUCACAGCAAUCUAAACAAGAUUCCCGAGGGUCUCCUUUGCUAGGUCCAGUUGUUCCAGGACCAUCUCCAAUCCCUUCUGUUACUGAAAAGAGGUUAUCAUCUGGCCAAAAUAAAGCUUCAGGCAAGAGGCAAAGAUCCAGUGGAAUAUGGGAGAAUGGUAGAGGACCAACACCUGCUACCCCAGAGAGCUUUUCUAAAAAAAGCAAGAAAGCAGUCAUGAGUGGUAUUCACCCUGCAGAAGACACGGAAGGUACUGAGUUUGAGCCAGAGGGACUUCCAGAAGUUGUAAAGAAAGGGUUUGCUGACAUCCCGACAGGAAAGACUAGCCCAUAUAUCCUGCGAAGAACAACCAUGGCAACUCGGACCAGCCCCCGCCUGGCUGCACAGAAGUUAGCGCUAUCCCCACUGAGUCUCGGCAAAGAAAAUCUUGCAGAGUCCUCCAAACCAACAGCUGGUGGCAGCAGAUCACAAAAGGUCAAAGUUGCUCAGCGGAGCCCAGUAGAUUCAGGCACCAUCCUCCGAGAACCCACCACGAAAUCCGUCCCAGUCAAUAAUCUUCCUGAGAGAAGUCCGACUGACAGCCCCAGAGAGGGCCUGAGGGUCAAGCGAGGCCGACUUGUCCCCAGCCCCAAAGCUGGACUGGAGUCCAACGGCAGUGAGAACUGUAAGGUCCAGUGAAGGCACUUUGUGUGUCAGUACCCCUGGGAGGUGCCAGUCAUUGAAUAGAUAAGGCUGUGCCUACAGGACUUCUCUUUAGUCAGGGCAUGCUUUAUUAGUGAGGAGAAAACAAUUCCUUAGAAGUCUUAAAUAUAUUGUACUCUUUAGAUCUCCCAUGUGUAGGUAUUGAAAAAGUUUGGAAGCACUGAUCACCUGUUAGCAUUGCCAUUCCUCUACUGCAAUGUAAAUAGUAUAAAGCUAUGUAUAUAAAGCUUUUUGGUAAUAUGUUACAAUUAAAAUGACAAGCACUAUAUCACAAUCUCUGUUUGUAUGUGGGUUUUACACUAAAAAAAUGCAAAACACAUUUUAUUCUUCUAAUUAACAGCUCCUAGGAAAAUGUAGACUUUUGCUUUAUGAUAUUCUAUCUGUAGUAUGAGGCAUGGAAUAGUUUUGUAUCGGGAAUUUCUCAGAGCUGAGUAAAAUGAAGGAAAAGCAUGUUAUGUGUUUUUAAGGAAAAUGUGCACACAUAUACAUGUAGGAGUGUUUAUCUUUCUCUUACAAUCUGUUUUAGACAUCUUUGCUUAUGAAACCUGUACAUAUGUGUGUGUGGGUAUGUGUUUAUUUCCAGUGAGGGCUGCAGGCUUCCUAGAGGUGUGCUAUACCAUGCGUCUGUCGUUGUGCUUUUUUCUGUUUUUAGACCAAUUUUUUACAGUUCUUUGGUAAGCAUUGUCGUAUCUGGUGAUGGAUUAACAUAUAGCCUUUGUUUUCUAAUAAAAUAGUCGCCUUCGUUUUCUGUAA